GACGCUGCCCCCGCUGCCCAAAAUGUCGGCGCCCAGAGGGAGGUGUAAGUAAUUAAAGAGGAAAGCCGACGGACUUCCCCGGCCUCCCGGGGCCGCCCCGGGUCUCCAGGACCAACGCUCCGUACGAGCGAGGUGGACUCGCCUGGCCCCGGGGCCUGCCCGACCUGCCCCCCAACCGGGCGCCCAGGGCUGCACCUUUUAGGGGCAGGGGGAGGGGCACAAAAGGCCGGCUCUCGGGGCCUGGGGCCUGGAGCAGACUGGGCAAGUGGGGGGGCCCGCUCCUCAGGCUGCGGGGUGGAGGAGGAGGCGGGGCCUAGUGGCUGCUGGGGCGGAGCAAGGGCUGGGAGGAGCCUGAGUUGGGCGGAGCUUAGAGUGGAAGUGGGAGGGGCGUGGAGGAGGGAGAGUCUGGAUAGAAAAUGGGAGGGUCUUAGGCAAAGAGGUGGGGUUUGAUAAAGGGGCGUGGCUCAGAAGGAAUGGUGGGUAGGCCCUGGAUUGAGGGGUGGAAGGAAACUCAUUGAGGCUGGUUGGGUAAAGGGAGCCCAGGAAGCAGGAGGGAGGAGUUUAGAGUAGAAGGGAUGGAGUUUGUCUGGGGUGUGGCUUAGAGAAGUAGGUAGGCCUAGUGAGGGGGGUGGAGUUUAAGGGUGUAAUUUGGAGGGGUUUAAUGCAACUAUCAGGUCUUUAUAAUGAAUGUGGAAAGGACUUGCAGGGGAUGGGAAUAGACUUCGUAGAGAAGGCCUGAGAAGGUGACGGGAGUCCAGUGGAGAGUCUUAGAAAGGAUGUGGCUUCUUUAAAGGAAAAAUUGGGUGGAGUUUUGGAAGUGGGUCUUAGUGGACCCGAGAGGGGCUUAGAUAAGUCAAAUAACUUAGCAAUCAUGGUAGGACUUAAGGAGGAAUCCAGGAGGAACUUACGGGAUAAUAGUCAUCCAAACAGCUUACUUGUUGCGUCUUUGCUGUGCACCAGCUUAAGUGGGCACGUAGCAUUUAUUGCCACAAUUUUACUUAAUUCUCGCCACCACUCCAUGAGGUAGGUACUACUAUUCCCAUUUUACAGAUGAAGAAUUUUUAUUAUCUGAUGUUACAGGAGUAAUUCUGGUCUCCCUGCAAGGAUGACUCCAGUGUGCUUAGCCCCAAAUCUUUGCCCUCCCAUUCGCUAAGUGGUCAUCCUGGAAGAGGAGUGGGAGGAGCUUAGAGGGGAGUGGGAGGGCCUUUUGGAAGGAAAAGGGCUUGGCAAAGAAUACAAGAUCCUUAGGGAACAUUGUGGGGGACUUUGAAGGGAGUAGGUGGGACUUAAGGAAGAGUGGGAGAGGCUUAAAUUACAGUGGGAGGGGCACAGAGAGCAGUGGCCGCGCAUUGGCGAAGAGCGAGGAGAGGCUUAAAAACACUCCGUGGAGUGAGGAGACUAUGAAGUGAUUAGGAAGAUUUUGCCACAGGCGUGGAGCCGCGAGAGAAGGGUUUCUAAGAGAGUAGGAGGAUUUUAAAGAACAAUGAGAGUGGCUUAGAGAGGUGGGCAGUGGGAGGGUCUCCCAGGGGACAGGUGGUGGGUCUGGGAACCUGGGAGGAGAGAGCUGAUGGGGAGCCGACCCCCUCACCUGCUCCUCUGUCUCCCCACUACUCCAGAGAGAGCCCCCACAUACCACUGUAUUCCCCGCCACCAUGGAUGACGUCCCCGCCCCAACCCCUGCACCAGCACCGCCCGCCGCUGCCGCCCCCAGGGUCCCGUUUCACUGCAGUGAAUGUGGCAAGAGCUUCCGCUACCGCUCAGACCUGCGGCGCCACUUUGCCCGGCACACAGCGCUCAAGCCCCACGCAUGUCCGCGCUGCGGCAAGGGUUUCAAGCACAGCUUCAACCUAGCCAACCACCUGCGCUCGCACACCGGGGAGCGGCCCUACCGCUGCUCUGCCUGCCCCAAGGGGUUCCGCGACUCCACCGGCCUGCUGCACCACCAGGUCGUCCACACUGGUGAGAAACCCUACUGCUGCCUGGUCUGCGAGCUCCGCUUCUCCUCACGCUCCAGCCUGGGCCGCCACCUCAAGCGCCAGCACCGUGGGGUUCUCCCCUCUCCCCUGCAGCCCGGCCCUGGCCUGCCCGCCUUGAGUGCGCCCUGCUCCGUCUGCUGCAAUGUGGGGCCCUGCUCGGUGUGCGGGGGCUCAGGGGCCGGCGGCGGAGAGGGCCCCGAGGGGGCAGGCGCGGGUCUGGGCAGCUGGGGGCUGGCAGAGGCGGCAGCUGCGGCCGCGGCCUCCUUGCCCCCAUUUGCGUGCGGCGCCUGCGCGCGGCGCUUCGACCACGGCCGCGAGCUGGCGGCCCACUGGGCGGCGCACACCGACGUGAAGCCCUUCAAGUGCCCGCGCUGCGAGCGCGACUUCAACGCGCCCGCGCUGCUGGAGCGGCACAAGCUGACGCACGACCUGCAGGGCCCGGGCGCGCCCCCAGCGCAGGCCUGGGCCGCGGGGCCAGGCGCAGGGCCCGAGACGGCGGGCGAAGGCACCGCUGCGGAGGCGGGCGACGCUCCUCUGGCUUCGGACCGCAGGCUGCUCCUGGGCCCCGCGGGGGGCGGCGUGCCCAAGCUCGGGGGGCUGCUCCCCGAGGGCGGUGGGGAGGCGCCUGCACCUGCGGCGGCCGCCGAGCCCUCGGAAGACACCCUGUACCAGUGCGACUGCGGGACCUUCUUUGCGUCGGCCGCGGCCCUGGCCAGUCACCUGGAGGCCCACUCGGGCCCGGCCACCUACGGCUGCGGCCACUGCGGGGCUCUGUACGCGGCGCUGGCCGCCUUGGAGGAGCACCGGCGGGUCAGCCACGGUGAGGGCGGCGGGGAGGAGGCGGCGACCGCCGCCCGGGAAAGGGAACCGGCGUCCGGGGAACCCCCGUCUGGCUCCGGCCGCGGCAAGAAGAUCUUCGGCUGCUCCGAGUGCGAGAAGCUGUUCCGCUCACCGCGAGACCUGGAGCGGCACGUGCUGGUGCACACUGGCGAGAAGCCGUUCCCGUGCCUGGAGUGCGGCAAGUUCUUCCGCCACGAGUGCUACCUCAAGCGCCACCGGCUGCUGCACGGCACCGAGCGGCCCUUCCCUUGCCACAUCUGCGGCAAGGGCUUCAUCACGCUCAGCAACCUCUCCAGGCACCUGAAGCUGCACCGGGGCAUGGACUGACUGCCAGGCUGCGUGCGCCCUGCCCUCCACCCAGCCUCCUGGACUCGGCCUGGACCAGGGGACCUCGGGACUGCGCGUGAGGCCCCGGCCCUCCAAAUCCAAAUCCAGACGCAGGCCCUGAAAUGAGGGGACCCUGACUGGAGAGGUGGGGGCCACCAAAAACCCACAAAGGCCCCGGAGCUGGGGGACCACAAACAAACAGGGUCCUUAGCUGGGGCAGGGGAGCCCAAAUCUAGGGAGAGACUCCUGAGCCUGAGGUCCCUGGAAUGAGUGUGGGUAGCCGUAAGUCCCCAAGACAUGGGGACUUUGCAGUGAGCAAUGGGUCUCCACAAGUACCUCUCAUCUUGAGAGCCCUAAUACUAAAAGAUGGGCACCCACCCCCACCAAGGGAAGACUGCCCCAUUCCCUGAGAGCCAUCAUUCCUAACGACCUUGAUCUGGAGAAUGUGGAGGGAGCAUGUCCCUGAAUUUUCCUAGAUCCCUCCAAAUGCCACCCACCAGAGUCACUGGUGACCCCAGAAAAUGGAUAUAGCCGAAAUCUGCCUUUCCCCUUUUUCAUUCCCUGUGCUGAAAGAGGGACCAGGGUAGAUGCCCCCUGCCCUCGAAUCCCCCCUCCCCGACUGUGGAAUGGAUCGACCCUAACGAUCUUCCCCGCCCCAAACACUAGAAUAGACUGGCCUGAAAUCCCCUUGCCCAGUAGAAUGGACUGAUCUAUGUGCACACACCCCCAUCACAUGGAAUGGGCUGGUCUAGGCUGUGGCCUGCCACCUUCCUUAGAGUGAAUAGGGCGGACACUCCUCUCUUUUCCUGUAGCGUGUGGACCGGUCCACGCAAUUCUUUAUCCUGUGAACUCAUCUGAGUGGGAGGUGGUGGACACUGGGGUUUCCUUCCCUCUCUCCGUAGCAUCCGUUGGUCUUUCUCUCCAUCUCUGUUGGUUUGUCUGUCUCUGUCUUCCUCCCAAUCCCUAGGGGAAGGGGGCAUUUGGCUAGGGGGUGCCCCUGUGAGCCUCGACCUUGCCCCCUCGUCCCUCUCCCCAGUGUUUCCAGGACCCCCAAUAAACCUUGUCCUGUCAGUC